CUCUCACGCAGCCAACAUGGCUCCAGUGGAGCACGUUGUGGCGGAUGCUGGGGCUUUCCUGCGGCAUGCGGCUCUGCAGGACAUCGGGAAGAACAUUUACACCAUCCGGGAGGUGGUCACUGAGAUUCGGGACAAGGCCACACGCAGGCGGCUCGCUGUCCUGCCCUACGAGCUGCGGUUCAAGGAGCCCUUACCGGAAUACGUGCGGCUGGUGACUGAGUUUUCAAAGAAAACAGGAGACUACCCCAGCCUCUCUGCCACGGACAUCCAAGUGCUUGCACUCACAUACCAGUUGGAAGCAGAGUUUGUUGGGGUGUCUCACCUAAAACAAGAACCACAGAAGGUUAAGGUGAGCUCAUCGAUUCAGCACCCAGAAACACCUCUGCACAUUUCUGGUUUCCAUCUGCCCUACAAGCCUAAACCCCCACAAGAAACAGAAAAAGGACACUCAGCUUGUGAGCCUGAGAACCUGGAAUUUAGUUCCUUCAUGUUCUGGAGAAACCCUUUGCCCAACAUCGAUCAUGAACUGCAGGAGCUGCUGAUUGACAGAGGUGAGGACGUUCCAAGUGAGGAGGAGGAGGAGGAAGAAAACGGGUUUGAAGACAGAAAAGAUGACAGCGAUGACGACGGGGGUGGCUGGAUAACCCCCAGUAACAUCAAGCAGAUCCAGCAGGAGCUGGAGCAGUGUGACGUCCCCGAGGACGUGCGGGUUGGCUGCCUGACCACAGACUUCGCCAUGCAGAAUGUUCUGCUGCAGAUGGGGCUGCACGUGCUGGCGGUGAACGGCAUGCUGAUUCGUGAGGCCCGGAGCUACAUCUUGCGCUGCCAUGGCUGUUUCAAGACAACGUCUGACAUGAGCCGAGUGUUCUGCUCACACUGUGGGAACAAGACCCUGAAGAAAGUGUCCGUGACCGUCAGCGACGACGGCACCCUGCACAUGCACUUCUCCCGCAACCCCAAGGUGCUGAACCCCCGCGGCCUCCGGUACUCGCUUCCCACUCCCAAAGGGGGCAAAUACGCCAUCAACCCCCAUCUCACCGAGGAUCAGCGCUUCCCUCAGCUGCGACUCUCCCAAAAGGCCAGGCAGAAAACCAACGUGUUCGCCCCUGACUACAUCGCCGGGGUGUCACCCUUUGUCGAGAAUGACAUCUCCAGCCGCUCAGCUACCCUGCAGGUCCGGGACAGCACCUUGGGAGCUGGGCGGAGACGCUUAAAUCCCAACGCUUCCAGAAAGAAGUUUGUGAAGAAAAGGUGAAGAGCGAGUUCCCGCAGGCAAAUUGGAUGGGCGUCUGGCCGCCGUGGAGUUCCGGUGACCCAUUUCCCCAGCCGUGUCGUCUCCAGGACCACCCGAUGGAAAUAACAGGCGGGCUUCACGGUGCGGCUCUGUCCGCCCAUGCCCCGCUGGGUCUGCAGGGAACUGGACUGUCCCAUGGCCUGUGAGCACCGGAGCGCCUGGCUGCCUGCCAAGGAAGUGCAAUUGCAUAAAAACAGAAAGAACAACGCCCUGGAGCCAAUCUUCAAGAAAGGAAUUUCCAAAGGAUAAUAUUUUUCUAAUAAAUGCGGCUGCAACCUCCUGUGCAUUUAAUUAAAUAGGCCAAAUUUUUGCUGCUUAGGUCAUCUCAAGGCUGAUACUUGAGCUGUGUGCCCAGAGAUCAUGCAUUUAGAUUUAUAUUUUUGCCAGAAAAUACAAGGUUAUAAUAAAACUAAGAACUACCA